AUGCCUAUAGCUAACGACACCCAGUUCCAUACUUCUUCAUUCCUACUGCUGGGUAUCCCAGGGCUAGAAGAUGUGCACAUCUGGAUUGGAUUCCCUUUUUUCUCUGUGUAUCUUAUUGCACUCCUGGGAAAUGCUGCUAUCUUCUUUGUGAUCCAAACUGAGCAGAGUCUCCAUGAGCCCAUGUACUACUGCCUGGCCAUGUUGGAUUCCAUUGACCUGAGCUUGUCUACGGCCACCAUUCCCAAAAUGCUGGGCAUCUUCUGGUUCAAUAUCAAGGAAAUAUCUUUUGGAGGCUACCUUUCUCAGAUGUUCUUCAUCCAUUUCUUCACUGUCAUGGAGAGCAUCGUAUUGGUGGCCAUGGCCUUUGACCGCUACAUUGCCAUUUGCAAACCUCUUUGGUACACCAUGAUCCUCACCAGCAAAAUCAUCAGCCUCAUUGCAGGCAUUGCUGUCCUGAGGAGCUUGUACAUGGUCAUUCCACUGGUGUUUCUCCUCUUAAGGUUGCCCUUCUGUGGACAUCGUAUCAUCCCUCAUACUUACUGUGAGCACAUGGGCAUUGCCCGUCUGGCCUGUGCCAGCAUCAAAGUCAACAUUAUGUUUGGUCUUGGCAGUAUUUCUCUCUUGUUAUUGGAUGUGCUCCUUAUUAUUCUCUCCCAUAUCAGGAUCCUCUAUGCUGUCUUCUGCCUGCCCUCCUGGGAAGCUCGACUCAAAGCUCUCAACACCUGUGGCUCUCACAUUGGUGUUAUCUUAGCCUUUUCUACACCAGCAUUUUUCUCUUUCUUUACACACUGCUUUGGCCAUGAUAUUCCCCAAUAUAUCCACAUUUUCUUGGCUAAUCUAUAUGUGGUUGUUCCUCCCACCCUCAAUCCUGUAAUCUAUGGGGUCAGAACCAAACAUAUUAGGGAGACAGUGCUGAGGAUUUUCUUCAAGACAGAUCACUAACCAGUUGGAGUUUGGAGGGUCUCUCUUA